ACUUCCACAGACUGCUUGCUGAGCAACUUCUGGAUCGCAUAUAAUUAGAAAAAGGAUAAAUAUAAUUGAAUCAAUAUUGAGAGAAUGGGAAAUGGGAAACAGGUCAAAAUGAGCAAGAGACGCAUGAGCGUGGGUCAGCAAACAUGGGCUCUUCUCUGCAAGAACUGUCUCAAAAAAUGGAGAAUGAAAAGACAGACCUUGUUGGAAUGGCUCUUUUCAUUUCUUCUGGUACUGUUUCUGUACCUAUUUUUCUCCAAUUUACAUCAAGUUCAUGACACUCCUCAAAUGUCUUCAAUGGAUCUGGGACGUGUAGAUAGUUUUAAUGAUACUAAUUAUGUUAUUGCAUUUGCACCUGAAUCCAAAACUACCCAAGAGAUAAUGAACAAAGUGGCUUCAGCCCCAUUCCUAAAAGGAAGAACAAUCAUGGGGUGGCCUGAUGAAAAAAGCAUGGAUGAAUUGGAUUUGAACUAUUCAAUAGACGCAGUGAGAGUCAUCUUUACUGAUACCUUCUCCUACCAUUUGAAGUUUUCUUGGGGACAUAGAAUCCCCAUGAUGAAAGAGCACAGAGACCAUUCAGCUCACUGUCAAGCAGUGAAUGAAAAAAUGAAGUGUGAAGGUUCAGAGUUCUGGGAGAAAGGCUUUGUAGCUUUUCAAGCUGCCAUUAAUGCUGCUAUCAUAGAAAUCGCAACAAAUCAUUCAGUGAUGGAACAGCUGAUGUCAGUUACUGGUGUACAUAUGAAGAUAUUACCUUUUGUUGCCCAAGGAGGAGUUGCAACUGAUUUUUUCAUUUUCUUUUGCAUUAUUUCUUUUUCUACAUUUAUAUACUAUGUAUCAGUCAAUGUUACACAAGAAAGACAAUACAUUACGUCAUUGAUGACAAUGAUGGGACUCCGAGAGUCAGCAUUCUGGCUUUCCUGGGGUUUGAUGUAUGCUGGCUUCAUCCUUAUCAUGGCCACUUUAAUGGCUCUUAUUGUAAAAUCUGCACAAAUUGUCGUCCUGACUGGUUUUGUGAUGGUCUUCACCCUCUUUCUCCUCUAUGGCCUGUCUUUGAUAACUUUAGCUUUCCUGAUGAGUGUGUUGAUAAAGAAACCUUUCCUUACGGGCUUGGUUGUGUUUCUCCUUAUUGUCUUUUGGGGGAUCCUGGGAUUCCCAGCAUUGUAUACACGUCUUCCUGCAUUUUUGGAAUGGACUUUGUGUCUUCUUAGCCCCUUUGCCUUCACUGUUGGGAUGGCCCAGCUUAUACAUUUGGACUAUGAUGUGAAUUCUAAUGCCCACUUGGAUUCUUCACAAAAUCCAUACCUCAUAAUAGCUACUCUUUUCAUGUUGGUUUUUGACACCCUUCUGUAUUUGGUAUUGACAUUAUAUUUUGACAAAAUUUUGCCCGCUGAAUAUGGACAUCGAUGUUCUCCCUUGUUUUUCCUGAAAUCCUGUUUUUGGUUUCAACACGGAAGGGCUAAUCAUGUGGUCCUUGAGAAUGAAACAGAUUCUGAUCCUACACCUAAUGACUGUUUUGAACCAGUGUCUCCAGAAUUCUGUGGGAAAGAAGCCAUCAGAAUCAAAAAUCUUAAAAAAGAAUAUGCAGGGAAGUGUGAGAGAGUAGAAGCUUUGAAAGGUGUGGUGUUUGACAUAUAUGAAGGCCAGAUCACUGCCCUCCUUGGUCACAGUGGAGCUGGAAAAACUACCCUGUUAAACAUACUUAGUGGGUUGUCAGUUCCAACAUCAGGUUCAGUCACUGUCUAUAAUCACACACUUUCAAGAAUGGCUGAUAUAGAAAAUAUCAGCAAGUUCACUGGAUUUUGUCCACAAUCCAAUGUGCAAUUUGGAUUUCUCACUGUGAAAGAAAACCUCAGGCUGUUUGCUAAAAUAAAAGGGAUUUUGCCACAUGAAGUGGAGAAAGAGGUACAACGAGUUGUACAGGAAUUAGAAAUGGAAAAUAUUCAAGACAUCCUUGCUCAAAACUUAAGUGGUGGACAAAAUAGGAAACUAACUUUUGGGAUUGCCAUUUUAGGAGAUCCUCAAGUUUUGCUAUUGGAUGAACCGACUGCUGGAUUGGAUCCUCUUUCAAGGCACCGAAUAUGGAAUCUCCUGAAAGAGGGGAAAUCAGACAGAGUAAUUCUCUUCAGCACCCAGUUUAUAGAUGAGGCUGACAUUCUGGCGGACAGGAAGGUGUUCAUAUCCAAUGGGAAGCUGAAGUGUGCAGGCUCUUCUCUGUUCCUUAAGAAGAAAUGGGGCAUAGGCUACCAUUUAAGUUUGCAUCUGAAUGAAAGGUGUGAUCCAGAGAGUAUAACAUCACUGGUUAAGCAGCACAUCUCUGAUGCCAAAUUGACAGCACAAAGUGAAGAAAAACUUGUAUAUAUUUUGCCUUUGGAAAGGACAAACAAAUUUCCAGAACUUUACAGGGAUCUUGAUAGAUGUUCUAACCAAGGCAUUGAGGAUUAUGGUGUUUCCAUAACAACUUUGAAUGAGGUGUUUCUGAAAUUAGAAGGAAAAUCAACUAUUGAUGAAUCAGAUAUUGGAAUUUGGGGACAAUUACAAACUGAUGGGGCAAAAGAUAUAGGAAGCCUUGUUGAGCUGGAACAAGUUUUGUCUUCCUUCCACGAAACAAGGAAAACAAUCAGUGGCGUGGCGCUCUGGAGGCAGCAGGUCUGUGCAAUAGCAAAAGUUCGCUUCCUAAAGUUAAAGAAAGAAAGAAAAAGCCUGUGGACUAUAUUAUUGCUUUUUGGUAUUAGCUUUAUCCCUCAACUUUUGGAACAUCUAUUCUACGAGUCAUAUCAGAAAAGUUACCCGUGGGAACUGUCUCCAAAUACAUACUUCCUCUCACCAGGACAACAACCACAGGAUCCUCUGACCCAUUUACUGGUCAUCAAUAAGACAGGGUCAACCAUUGAUAACUUUUUACAUUCACUGAGGCGACAGAACAUAGCUAUAGAAGUGGAUGCCUUUGGAACUAGAAAUGGCACAGAUGACCCAUCUUACAAUGGUGCUAUCAUUGUGUCAGGUGAUGAAAAGGAUCACAGAUUUUCAAUAGCAUGUAAUACAAAACGGCUGAAUUGCUUUCCUGUCCUCCUGGAUGUCAUUAGCAAUGGACUACUUGGAAUUUUUAAUUCGUCAGAACACAUUCAGACUGACAGAAGCACAUUUUUUGAAGAGCAUAUGGAUUAUGAGUAUGGGUACCGAAGUAACACCUUCUUCUGGAUACCGAUGGCAGCCUCUUUCACUCCAUACAUUGCAAUGAGCAGCAUUGGUGACUACAAAAAAAAAGCUCAUUCCCAGCUACGGAUUUCAGGCCUCUACCCUUCUGCAUACUGGUUUGGCCAAGCACUGGUGGAUGUUUCCCUGUACUUUUUGAUCCUCCUGCUAAUGCAAAUAAUGGAUUAUAUUUUUAGCCCAGAGGAGAUUAUAUUUAUAAUUCAAAACCUGUUAAUUCAAAUCCUGUGUAGUAUUGGCUAUGUCUCAUCUCUUGUUUUCUUGACAUAUGUGAUUUCAUUCAUUUUUCGCAAUGGGAGAAAAAAUAGUGGCAUUUGGUCAUUUUUCUUCUUAAUUGUGGUCAUCUUCUCGAUAGUUGCUACUGAUCUAAAUGAAUAUGGAUUUCUAGGGCUAUUUUUUGGCACCAUGUUAAUACCUCCCUUCACAUUGAUUGGCUCUCUAUUCAUUUUUUCUGAGAUUUCUCCUGAUUCCAUGGAUUACUUAGGAGCUUCAGAAUCUGAAAUUGUAUACCUGGCACUGCUAAUACCUUACCUUCAUUUUCUCAUUUUUCUUUUCAUUCUGCGAUGCCUAGAAAUGAACUGCAGGAAGAAACUAAUGAGAAAGGAUCCUGUGUUCAGAAUUUCUCCAAGAAGCAACGCUAUUUUUCCAAACCCAGAAGAGCCUGAAGGAGAGGAGGAAGAUAUCCAGAUGGAAAGAAUGAGAACAGUGAAUGCUAUGGCUGUGCGAGACUUUGAUGAGACACCCGUCAUCAUUGCCAGCUGUCUACGGAAGGAAUAUGCAGGCAAAAAGAAAAAUUGCUUUUCUAAAAGGAAGAAAAAAAUUGCCACAAGAAAUGUCUCUUUUUGUGUUAAAAAAGGUGAAGUUAUAGGACUGUUAGGACACAAUGGAGCUGGUAAAAGUACAACUAUUAAGAUGAUAACUGGAGACACAAAACCAACUGCAGGACAGGUGAUUUUGAAAGGGAGCGGUGGAGGGGAACCCCUGGGCUUCCUGGGGUACUGCCCUCAGGAGAAUGCGCUGUGGCCCAACCUGACAGUGAGGCAGCACCUGGAGGUGUACGCUGCCGUGAAAGGUCUCAGGAAAGGGGACGCAAUGAUCGCCAUCACACGGUUAGUGGAUGCGCUCAAGCUGCAGGACCAGCUGAAGGCUCCCGUGAAGACCUUGUCAGAGGGAAUAAAGCGAAAGCUGUGCUUUGUGCUGAGCAUCCUGGGGAACCCGUCAGUGGUGCUUCUGGAUGAGCCGUCGACCGGGAUGGACCCCGAGGGGCAGCAGCAAAUGUGGCAGGUGAUUCGGGCCACCUUUAGAAACACGGAGAGGGGCGCCCUCCUGACCACCCACUACAUGGCAGAGGCUGAGGCGGUGUGUGACCGAGUGGCCAUCAUGGUGUCAGGAAGGCUGAGAUGUAUUGGUUCCAUCCAACACCUGAAAAGCAAAUUUGGCAAAGACUACCUGCUGGAGAUGAAGCUGAAGAACCUGGCACAAAUGGAGCCCCUCCAUGCAGAGAUCCUGAGGCUUUUCCCCCAGGCUGCUCAGCAGGAAAGGUUCUCCUCCCUGAUGGUCUAUAAGUUGCCUGUUGAGGAUGUGCGACCUUUAUCACAGGCUUUCUUCAAAUUAGAGAUAGUUAAACAGAGUUUCGACCUGGAGGAGUACAGCCUCUCACAGUCUACCCUGGAGCAGGUUUUCCUGGAGCUCUCCAAGGAGCAGGAGCUGGGUGAUCUUGAAGAGGACUUUGAUCCCUCGGUGAAGUGGAAACUCCUCCUGCAGGAAGAGCCUUAAAGCUCCAAAUACCCUAUAUCUUUCUUUAAUCCUGUGACUCUUUUAAAGAUAAUAUUUUAUAGCCUUAAUAUGCCUUAUAUCAGAGGUGGUACAAAAUGCAUUUGAAACUCAUGCAAUAAUUAUCCUCAGUAGUAUUUCUUACAGUGAGACAACAGGCGAUGUCAGUGAGGGCGAUCAUAGGGCAUAAGCCUAAGCCAUACCAUGCAGCCUUUGUGCCAGCAACCAAAUCCCAUGUUUCCUACUGUGUUAAGUUUAAAAAUGCAUUUAUUAUAGAAUUGUCUACAUUUCUGAGGAUGUCAUGGAGAAUGCUUAAUUUUCUUUCUCUGAACUUCAAAAUAUUAAAUAUUUUCUUAUUUAUUUUUUUGAUUAAAGUAUAAAUUAAGACACCCUAUUGACUUCCGGGUAAGGGGAGUCAAUUGAUUACCCAGCAGCACAGUAUUUGCUUUUUAUAAUUCCCUUUUUAAAUACUUGUUCUUAAUUCACUGGUUUUCCUUUUCUGUCAUUUUUCAGAGUUUAGAUUGUGAGUCCAUGUUUUGUCUGUUGUGCCUAUAAAGGAAAUUUGAAAUCUGUAUCAUUCUACUAUAAAGACACAUGCACACGUAUGUUUAUUGCAGCACUGUUUACAAUAGCAAAGACUUGGAACCAACCAAAAUACCCACAAAUGAUAGACCGGAUAAAGAAAACGUGACACAUAUACACCAUGGAAUACUAUGCAGCCAUAGAAAAGGAUGAGUUCAUAUUCUUCACAGGGACAUGGAUGAAGCUGGAAACCAUCAUCCUCAGCAAACUAACACAGGAACAGAAAACCAAACACCGCAUGUUCUCACUCAUAAGUGGGAAUUGAACAAUGAGAAUACAUGGACACAGGGAGGGGAACACCACACCCUGGGGCCUGUUGGGGGGAUGGGGGCUAGGGGAGGGAUAGCAUUAGGAGAAAUACCUGAUGUAGAUGAUGGGUUGAUGGGUGCAGCAAAGUACCAUGGCACAUGUAUACCUGUGUAACAAACCUGCACAUUCAGCACAUGUAUCCCAGAACUUAAAGUAUAAUAAAAAUAAAUAAAUAAUUUCAGUAAGAACCUGAUCAAGUUGAACAUGUAUAUAUAUGUUAUACACAAGUUUGAAACAUAUUUCUGUUUUUAUAUGUUUUCUUAUGAUGCAAGGGCAUACUCUUAUGCAAAUAAUUAAAACUUCAUAGGUCUUAAUUUCCCAUAUCUCUAUAUAUUAUUAUGACCUAUCCAACUGGUAACCCUAUGAACACCUUAAAAUAAACUUGUAUACUCUUAUUUAGGUGAGUUUUUCUUGUUAAUACUAUUAUUAUUGCUAUCUAAUUGAAUACUUGAAGGAAGUUGUGUGAAAGACCUUGGCUUUGAUUUUAGUUCUUAUAUUCUUCUAGUUUUUGAAAAUAAAACACUUCCAUCAACCCGUAA